GGUGGUGCUGUGGUCUGCCCCUGGAGAACCCAGAAGAACACAGCUGUGCGCGCCCACAGGCUCUGGGGGCGGGAGAAGAUAAGUCGCAAGGAGGGGGCGGGACCUACACCUCAGGAAAGCCGGAGAAUUGGGGCACGAAGCGGGGCUUUGAUGACCCGCAAAGGGCGAGGCAUGCAGGAGGUGGAGGAAUUAAGUGAAACAGGGAAGGUUGUUAAACAGCACCGUGUGGGCGAGGCCUUAAGGGUCGUGGUCCUUGUCUGGGCGGGGUCUUUGGGCGUCGACGAGGCCUGGUUCUGGGUAGGCGGGGCUACUACGGGGCGGUGCCUGCUGUGGAAAUGCCUGCCCGCGCGCUUCUGCCCAGGCGCAUGGGGCAUCGUACUCUAGCCUCCACUCCUGCCCUGUGGGCCUCCAUCCCGUGCCCUCGCUCUGAGCUGCGCCUGGACCUGGUUCUGCCUUCUGGACAAUCUUUCCGGUGGAGGGAGCAAAGUCCUGCACACUGGAGUGGUGUACUAGCGGAUCAAGUAUGGACACUGACUCAGACUGAGGAGCAGCUCCACUGCACUGUGUACCGAGGAGACAAGAGCCAGGCUAGCAGGCCCACACCAGACGAGCUGGAGGCCGUGCGCAAGUACUUCCAGCUAGAUGUUACCCUGGCUCAACUGUAUCACCACUGGGGUUCCGUGGACUCCCACUUCCAAGAGGUGGCUCAGAAAUUCCAAGGUGUGCGACUGCUGCGACAAGACCCCAUCGAAUGCCUUUUCUCUUUUAUCUGUUCCUCCAACAACAACAUCGCCCGCAUCACUGGCAUGGUGGAGCGGCUGUGCCAGGCUUUUGGACCUCGGCUCAUCCAGCUUGAUGAUGUCACCUACCAUGGCUUCCCCAGCCUGCAGGCCCUGGCUGGGCCAGAGGUGGAGGCUCAUCUCAGGAAGCUGGGCCUGGGCUAUCGUGCCCGUUACGUGAGUGCCAGUGCCCGAGCCAUCCUGGAAGAACAGGGCGGGCUAGCCUGGCUGCAGCAGCUACGAGAGUCCUCAUAUGAGGAGGCCCACAAGGCCCUCUGCAUCCUGCCUGGAGUGGGCACCAAGGAAACUUUUUCCGGAGCCUGUGGGGACCUUAUGCUGGCUGGGCCCAAGCGGUGUUCCGGUGCCAGCAGAAGGCCUGCUUACGUCGGCAUCUGCAUUCCAGAGCCCCCUAAGGUCUAGGCAGCCUGAGGCUGACAGGAGGUGGGUGAGACACCAGAUCAAUCUCUCUGAACAGGGUCUGAUUUAUACAUUUCAUCGAUGGUGGAGCUGGAAGGUCACUUAGUGAUUGAGUCCAGCCUGCCAGUUUUCCAGAAGGGGAAGGAGAUGCUCAGGUCAGGGGCUGCUUAAGGCCUUGCAGCUGCUCUGCAGCAGGGUAAGGGCUGUGCUCUGGUUUCCUGAGAGCUGCAAGCCAUUUCUUCAUUGCCCAUUACUUCUUUUUUUUUUUUUUUUUUUUUUUUUGAGACAGGUCUCACUCUGUCACCCAGGCUGGAGUACAGUGGCCUGAUCAAGCUCACUGCAGCCUCUACCUCCCAGGAUCAAGCAAUCCUCCCACAUCAGCCUCCUGAGUAGGACUAUAGGCAUGUGCCACCAUGCCUAGCUGAUUUUUAAAAAUUUUUAGUAGAGAAGGGGGUCUGACUACAUUGCCCAGGCUAGUUUCGAACUCCUGAGCUCAAACAAGCCUCCCACCUCAGUCUCCCAAAGUGCUGGGAUUACAGGCAUGAGCCACCAGGCCCAGCUAGGGCCCACUACUUCUGUAACUGCACAUGCCUGCUUUUCUCUCUCUUCCUCUCUCUCCCUCUGCUUCCCUCAGUGCCUCUUCCAUCUGUGUUUUCUUCUUCUCACCUUUCAGAGAAAACAAACUAUUAUAGAAAGAGGCUUUGAUUCAACCACAGGUUCAAGUCUCAGCUUGCUGUUUAUUGACUGUGUGACCUUCAGCAGAGCAUUUCGCUUCACUGGGCCUUUAUUUCCUCAUCUGGUAAACAACGAAAAUAGCUCCUCCCUCCUGGGUUGUUGUCAAGACACUUGAGAGAGUGUACAUAAAGCCCCUGACACACAGUAGGCCCUCAGCAUACAUUAGUCACUCUUAUCCUUAAAUACCCUGGCAGCUUGUCAGCAACUACCUCUCCUUUUAAUGGCACUUAUCUUUACUGAUCAUCUGCUAGUAAUCUGCAAGUCCCUUGCUCUGCCUCUCUUGCUGGCCCCCAGCACAAUAUCUAAGAGACAGUAAGAAUGGCCAAAUGAUUAGCCUGGCAUGGUAGUGCAUGCCUGUAAUCCCAACUACUCAGGAGGCUGAGGCAGGAGAACUGCCUGAACCCGGGAGGCGGAGGUUGCAGUGAGCCGAGAUCAUGGCACUGCACUCCAGCCUGGGCAACAGAGUGAGACACCGUCUCAAAAAAAAAAAAAAAAGGCCAAAUGAAUGAAUGUGCCCUGUCCUGUCAGGGCUCUAUGAAGUUAAGACACAGCACUUGUCUGUGAGAAGCAAAGAGACUUGUUCGGGUUGCUUCCCUAUCUCUUUACCUAAAGGGUAGCUAUUCCACAGUCUUCCUCAAGAUGUCACCUAUACCCUCGUGAUCAAUGCAGAACAAGAUGGAUGGGAGUUGACAUCAAAUGAAUGGCAGGCACUGUGAUGGAUUCCCAAAAGAACAUGUCCUAAAACACUGGUCAAUUUCUUGUGAUGAGCAAAUAAAAAUCACAGAUCUCCAACAAAA